AGUGUACACGUCGGUUGCCUAACAACCGGCAGCGGACUCCUUUGGCUAUGGCCUCCAACUUUAAGAAGGCAAACAUGGCAUCAAGUUCUCAGCGAAAAAGAAUGAGCCCUAAGCCUGAGCUUACUGAAGAGCAAAAGCAGGAGAUCCGGGAAGCUUUUGAUCUUUUCGAUGCGGAUGGAACUGGCACCAUAGAUGUUAAAGAACUGAAGGUGGCAAUGAGGGCCCUGGGCUUUGAACCCAAGAAAGAAGAAAUUAAGAAAAUGAUAAGUGAAAUUGAUAAGGAAGGGACAGGAAAAAUGAACUUUGGUGACUUUUUAACUGUGAUGACCCAGAAAAUGUCUGAGAAAGAUACUAAAGAAGAAAUCCUGAAAGCUUUCAAGCUCUUUGAUGAUGAUGAAACUGGGAAGAUUUCGUUCAAAAAUCUGAAACGCGUGGCCAAGGAGUUGGGUGAGAACCUGACUGAUGAGGAGCUGCAGGAAAUGAUUGAUGAAGCUGAUCGAGAUGGAGAUGGAGAGGUCAGUGAGCAAGAGUUCCUGCGCAUCAUGAAAAAGACCAGCCUCUAUUAAGAUCAGUGUCUUCUUUUUCUACUGCAAGCACAUGUAACUAGAUUUAGUGCCUGCCAUGGUGUGAAAUCUGGCUUUUGAGAACACAAACUUUUCCCCCACGGACCUCCCUUUAUCACUUUAAUAGUGACCUUGAGCCUAUUUUAGCCGUUUGGAAGUGUUCUUUGAUAUUACAGUUCUUUGUAAAAUGACCUGCGAAUUACCCUAAUUCUCAAAAGCAAAACAAGAGCACACAAGCGUGAAGAAAAGGAUCUUAAAGCUUUGAGCACCUGCCAUUUUGCCUUGCAUCGUUUCCCUCGUCAUGCAUUUCCACAUAUCCACAAACACAGAACGACUUUAGACAAGCACAUGUUACACCUGUGUUGCCACAAGCAGUCAUUCUUGACGGCUCCAGUUUUUAUUUGACACUUGAGUUUAGUUUUCUCUUUUAUAAACCCAGUGAACUCCUGCACUGGCAUUUGGAUGUGUGUUAAUGCUAUUUGUUUUGUCUUAAAAGUAAAACCUUUCUCAGUUUGAACUUGUAUUCUCUAAGGAUGAGUUCUUUAGCUUUGCUUAUGAGUUCCUCUUCUCAAUUAUUGUGUUGAAGGCAGCCUAUUAGAUACAAAACUCCUUACCAGCCUAUGGACAGAAAAUGAAUAAUCCUUUGCUACUUUCCUGGCAUGAAUUGCUUUUUGCCUUGGAAGGCUGCUGGUUUGUAAAACUAGCAGAAUUUUUAUAUCACCUAAGCCUAAAUGAUGCUCUAAAAAUAGUUUUGGCAAAGCUAAGACUGGAAAAGAGUCUUGUUAGUAAUUUGUGCUUGAAUAAAAUGGGGAGAGCCAGGCUAACGCAACACUAGGAUGGAUUCAGCCAA